GUCUUUGUCUCUCGCUGUAGCCGGAGCUCCAGGUUUUGCUCUCACUUCUCUGUGUCUUCUGCUCCUAGGGGCCUAGCCUGUGUGGCCCUCUGACCUGCAGAUAUUGGGAGAUCCACAGCUAAGACGCCAGGACCCCCUAGAAGCCUAGAAAUGGAUGACCCGAGGUAUGGAAUGUGUCCUCUCAAGGGAGCAAGUGGAUGCCCUGGGGCUGAGAGGAGUCUUCUGGUGCAGUCUUAUUUUGAAAAGGGGCCAUUGACGUUUAGGGAUGUGGCCAUAGAAUUCUCUCUGGAGGAGUGGCAAUGCCUGGACAGUGCUCAGCAGGGUUUGUAUAGGAAAGUGAUGUUAGAGAACUACAGAAACCUGGUCUUCUUGGCAGGUAUUGCUCUCACUAAGCCAGACCUGAUCACCUGUCUGGAGCAAGGAAAAGAGCCCUGGAAUAUAAAGAGACAUGAGAUGGUAGCCAAACCCCCAGUUAUAUGUUCUCAUUUUCCCCAAGACCUUUGGGCAGAGCAGGACAUUAAAGAUUCUUUUCAAGAAGCGAUUCUGAAAAAAUAUGGAAAAUAUGGACAUGACAAUUUACAGUUACAAAAAGGCUGUAAAAGUGUGGAUGAGUGUAAAGUGCACAAAGAACAUGAUAACAAAUUAAACCAGUGUUUGAUAACUACCCAGAGCAACAUAUUUCAAUGUGAUCCAUCUGCAAAAGUCUUUCAUACAUUUUCAAAUUCAAACAGACAUAAGAUAAGACAUACUAGAAAGAAACCUUUCAAAUGUAAAAAAUGUGAAAAAUCAUUUUGCAUGCUUUUACACCUAACUCAACAUAAAAGAUUUCAUAUUACAGAGAAUUCCUACCAAUGUAAAGAUUGUGGCAAAGCCUUCAACUGGUUCUCAACCCUUACUACACACAGGAGAAUUCAUACUGGAGAGAAACCCUACAAAUGUGAAGAAUGUGGGAAAGCAUUUAACCGGUCCUCACACCUUACUACACAUAAGAUAAUUCAUACUGGAGAGAAACCAUACAGAUGUGAAGAAUGUGGGAAAGCUUUUAACCGGUCUUCACACCUUACUACACAUAAAAGAAUUCAUACUGGAGUGAAACCCUACAAAUGUACAGAAUGUGGCAAAGCUUUUAACCGGUCCUCACACCUUACUACACACAGGAUAAUUCAUACUGGAGAGAAACCCUACAAAUGUGAAGAAUGUGGCAAAGCCUUUAACCAGUCCUCAACCCUUACUACACAUAAGAUAACUCAUGCUGGAGAGAAACCUUACAAAUGUGAAGAAUGUGGCAAAGCUUUUUACCGAUUCUCAUACCUUACUAAACAUAAGACAAGUCAUACUGGAGAGAAAUUCUACAAAUGUGAAGAAUGCGGCAAAGGCUUUAACUGGUCCUCAGCCCUCACUAAACAUAAGAGAAUUCAUACUGGAGAGAAACCCUACAAAUGUGAAGAAUGUGGCAAAGCUUUUAAUGAGUCCUCAAACCUUACUACCCAUAAGAUGAUUCAUACUGGAGAGAAACCCUACAAAUGUGACGAAUGUGGCAAAGCCUUUAACCGGUCCUCACAACUAACUGCACAUAAGAUGAUUCAUACUGGAGAGAAACCCUACAAAUGUGAGGAAUGUGGCAAAGCUUUUAACCGAUCCUCAACCCUUACUAAACAUAAGAUAACUCAUACUGGAGAGAAAUCUUACAAAUGGGAAGAAUGUGGUAAAGACUUUAACCAGUCCCUAAGCCUUAUUAAACAAAAUAACUCAUACUGGAGAGAAACCCUACAAAUGUGAAAAAUGUGGCAAAGCCUUUUACCAGUCCUCAACUCUUACUAAACAUAAAAAAAUUCAUACUGGAGGGAACUCCUGUGACUGUGAAGAAUAUGGCAAAGCCUUUAAUAAAUUCUCAAUUCCUAACAGACAUAAGAUAAUUCAUACUAGAGAGAAAUUCUACAAACCAGAAAGAUGUGACAGUGCUUUGAAAACACCUCAAACUUUUCAAAACAUAAAUCAUAGUGUUGAGAAAUCCUAGAAAUGUGAAGAAUGUGAUAAAGUUUUAAAUGGUUGUCACACUUGAUUGUAGGUAAGGUAAGUUAUACUGGAGAAAACUUCUACAUGUGUGAACAGUGUGACAAAACUUUUAACUAAUGCUCACACCUUCACAGGAAAGCAUUUAUACUUGAGAAAUAUUGUACAAAUAUAAAGACUGUGAAAAAGCCAUUAAUACAUGCUCACAUCUUACUCAACAUCAGAGAGUUCAUACUCAAUAAAAACAUAAGUGCAACUACUGUCAAAAUAUCUUUAAGAAAAUAUAAGCUUUUAAAGUGAAGAGUAUUUUGAAGAAGAACAUUGUAGUAGAAUUGUAAUAUGUUUACUUGUAUCACAGAUCUUACUGUACACGUUUUGUAUUAGAGGAAACCUCUGAAGCAGUUGCUCAAACUUUGUUCAAUAUCAGGGAAUUUAUAUUGAAAAAAACUGUGCGAAUGUAAUAAAGUUGGAAAAAUACUUUUUCAAAAACUACAGCUUAGAAAACACCAGAGAGUUCAUACUAAAACAUAUUUUUGCAGAUACAGGAAAAAUUUUUUAAAAAUUUUAAUCAUUAAGUCUGUAAAUAUCAGAGAAUUUACAGUAGAAAUAUGUAAGGCACUGAUGCUUCAGGUAUUUUACUAAAUCAGAGUGCUGAGUAUAGAAAAUAAUCUAAAACUAAAAUUGGUAAAAUAUUUGUAUAUAACUUUAAAAGUAGAAAUUUUUUGCAGUUAUUGCAUUCAAAGUAUGCUUAACUUUUUGAAAAAAUUAGAUUUUUUGAAAAGUGAGUAAUAAUGUAAUUCAACUCUUAAAUUAUUUCCUGCCUUUUCUUCACUCCUAUUUACAUGUGAAAGCAUGUGAUCAAUUGUUGCUGCAUCAGAUAUGAGAGAUUCUUUUUUAUUAGGUGAGCAUUAUUUAUAAACUUUGCUAUGAAAAAGACAUUAAAAUAUGAGAUGUAUGAUGAAAAUCUAAGUGAAGAGACUUUUAUGGUUAACUUAUAAUAUUAAGCAAUGUGUGCGUUAGGCAUUCAGAGUAAUAUUCUGCAUUAUGAGAAAACUUAAUUUCAUUUAUAAGUAAAUUAAAAUUAGUAUAUUUUACUAAUACUUUUAUAUAAAAUGCAGUAUAUUUUUUAAAUUUCAGAUUAUAUGUGAUGUUAAUAUAUUCAACCUUUUUAACAUGUUAAAUACUAUUGUGCAUUCAGUGAAGUGUUAUUAUGCCACAGACAUUAACCUAUUCCACCUUACUCAAGGGUGUACGUAAAACAUGGUAACAGUAUACUAUUUGGUAACAUAAUGGAUUAACAUCUCUAGUAAUCUCUUUUGCUAGUGGCUUUGACUGCAAAUAAGUUAAAGAAUAUUAUUUCUGUAGGUUAAAUUUUUGUUUUUAUUUUAUUUUAUUUUUGAGAGGUAGUCUUGCUCUGUCACCCAGGCUGGAGUGCAGUGGCACGAUCUCGGCUCACUGUAACCUCCACCUCCUGGGUUCACGCAAUUCUCCUGCCUCAGCCUCCUAAGUAGCUGGGAUUACAGGCACCCACCACCAUGCCCAGCUAAUUUUUGUAUUUUAGUAGAGACAGGGUUUCAUAAUGUAAGUCAAGCUGGUCUCGAACUCCUGACCUUAAAUGAUUUGCCUGCCUCGGCUUCCCAAAGUUCUGGGAUUACAGGCAUGAGCCACCGUGCCCAGCCAAAUGUUUAUUUUAUUUAAAUUUAUUUUUCUUAAUUAUUUGGGGUACAUAAUAUGAGUAUAUAUUCAUGCAAUAUAUGGCAUAUUUUGAUACAAGAAUACAGUAUAUAAUAAUCACAUCAGGGUAAAUGAGGUAUCCAUCACCUCUAGUAUUUAUCCUUUGUAUUACAAGCAACCCAGUUUUAUACUUUUAGUUAUUUUAAAAUGUAAAAUUAAAUUGUUAUUGAUUACAGUGUUAUUUUUAUGGUCAUAAUAAAAGUUAUGUAGAAGUAUAAUAAAAUCCCUACAUUUCUGAGGCCUGAAUAAGUAUUUUUAAAGUUUUCUAAUAUUUAUUUUUUGAGCAUGUUUCCUGUCUGCCUGCAAACACAUGCAGACAUUUAGUUUUGAUUUACAUAUAGUUAAAUAUAUGUUAGUCUAAAGAUAAACCUUAAGUGUAAGAAAAUUAUAGAGUGAGUUUGUGUGUAUGAAUUUGUACCUGUUUUCCGAAGAAAAAAGCAAUACUGAACAAAACAAAUCAUUUUAACAAGAUGACUACUAGAAAACUAAAAGCCUCAAAAAUGCUAAAAGAAAAUGUAUUCUCUGCUUUGUAUUGAAUUUAUUACUGUACAUUCUGUGGCUUAUAGUUCUGAAUCUCCCCAUGAAAAUUCUGUUUAUACUUGCCUGGUACUCAUGAUAGACCCCUAAUUAUUUUGUAUCUUUUUUCAUAUAAAUAUUUUACAGAUUAUGAAGUAUUCAUUAUGUGAGCUGGUCUGUGAUUAUAAGAAUAAUUUUUACAAAAUUUAGUGCAUACAAAAUUUUUAAAUGUAAUUCCACAAUUAGUGUAUUAAGUUACAUUUUAUUUAGUUAGAACACUUCAUUUUGUUUUUAGUUGGAGAACUCUAUAGCCCUUUAGUUAUUUUUCUUUUCACUUUUUAUAGUUGACAUAAGUAAAUUUAUUUAUUGAGUCAAUUUGUUCAGGUAAGUACUAGGGAAGCUUUAUAAGUCGUGAGGAUGUUUUUAUAUUUAAAUGUAGCAAACAUACAUGACAGUUCUUGCUGUGUAACAGAUGCUCCAUAGUAAGCCAUAAGUAUUCCUGCUAAAGUUAGCUUGUAACUUCAGUUCAGAGAUGGAAAACAUCAGUGGUGAAGAAAUAAAAUUGAUUCUUCAUGUGGAGAGGACAUAGUUUCCAGGCUGCAAUGCUGAAUCUUGCUGAAUUUAAAGAGAAGUUCUGCAUCUUUUAUUUCUUAAUUAUCUUCAGAUUUCUCUGUAUUUAUUAUGUGUAUCCCCAGCUAUGUAUGCAGCACAGCCCAUCUCCUUUUUCUGUGUUAUGGCUUCAGUUUUCUCACUGUUGUCUUAAUGCCAUUUCAUUUCACAUGGUACUUUGUAAAUUUUGACGAGAAAGUUGGUUGUUUUUUUUUUUUUUUUUUUUUUUGAGACAGAGUCUCACUCUUGUUGCCCAAGCUGGAGUGCAGUGGUGCAAUGUGGGCUCACUGCAACCUCUGCCUUCCAGGUUCAAGCAAUUAUCCUGCCUCAGCCUCCCAAGUAGCUGGGAUUACAGGCACCUGCCACCACAUCUGGCUGAAUUUUUUUUUUUUUAAUUUUUUGUAGAGACGAAGUUUCACCAUGUUGGCCAGGCUGGUUUCAAACUCCUGACCUCAUAUGAUCCACCUGCCUCAGCCUCCCAAAGUGCUUGGAUUACAGGCAUAAGCCACUGCACCCAGCUGAAAGUUGGUAUUUUUUAAUGCACUGAAUAAUUGUUUUUAACUGGAGAGUUUGGUUAUCAAUAUAACUUUCGGAUUAGUUAAGAUAAAAGCAUACAUUGUCCACAGGUGAGAAGAUUAAAUCAGAAUAGUUGUUCUUUGUUAAAAAAAAAAUUAGAUUCUUAAAGUGUGGCAAACAUAAAAUUUGCAAGAAAAUGUAGAAAUUAAAUUUUUAAGAGUUAAUGGUAAGUGAACAAUUUUAAAUUUAUUUUUUAUUAUGUAACAUACUUUUAUUAAAAUAUAUACUUAUAUAAUAAAAGUA